GCGUCUCUGGCCUCGCCGGUCUUGGGGGGAUGGUUCCAUCAUGGCGUCAAUGCAGACCACAGGAAGGAGGGUGGAAGUAUGGUUUCCAAAACGACUACAGAAAGAACUGUUGGCUUUGCAAAAUGACCCACCUCCUGGAAUGACCUUAAAUGAGAAGAGUGUUCAAAAUUCAAUUACACAGUGGAUUGUAGACAUGGAAGGUGCACCAGGUACCUUAUAUGAAGGGGAAAAAUUUCAACUUCUAUUUAAAUUUAGUAGUCGAUAUCCUUUUGACUCUCCUCAGGUCAUGUUUACUGGUGAAAAUAUUCCUGUUCAUCCUCAUGUUUAUAGCAAUGGUCAUAUCUGUUUAUCCAUUCUAACAGAAGACUGGUCCCCAGCGCUCUCAGUCCAAUCAGUUUGUCUUAGCAUUAUUAGCAUGCUUUCCAGCUGCAAGGAAAAGAGACGACCACCGGAUAAUUCUUUUUAUGUGCGAACAUGUAACAAGAAUCCAAAGAAAACAAAAUGGUGGUAUCAUGAUGAUACUUGUUGAUGCCACUGUUAUCAUCCUCCUAGCAGAAGAUAGUCCUACUGAGAAAAUGAGCACUUUGAUCAUUCAGUCUUUGAACUUUAACCUUUGACUGGAAGUGACCUAUAGGCAAUGAAGACUACUUCCUUUUACUGCAUUUUUACUCGUGUGCAUUCUGGGCGCAUGUUGAUCGCUGGUUCAGUCCAGGCAACUGACAUGCUUUUAUUAGUCAUACAGUAUUAAUGCAGGUGUCAGGAAAUGUCAAAUAUAAUUCCAUUUUUUAUUUUUAUUUUUUUAAGCUUUUGGAAAAGCUCCAGGUCCUCAUGUAUUGUGCAAUAACAAUGACUUCCUUGGCGGUUUUGGUACGUUCAUUGCCGGCAAUGGGCGUUGUAACAGGAAAAGUUUUCAUUAACUCCUGCCAUUCAAUGAUUAAUGCAUGAUAGGGCCUAUGAAAUGAACUUACUGGUUAUAGUGGGAAUAUAAAUAAAGUGAGGGAUCCAACAUUACUUUAAAAGUCACCCCAACUGUUUAUAUUUGGAUUCUAUGCACUGUGAUCCUAAGGUUAACAGCAUGAAUUAACAUGCGUCUUUAAAGGACUGUAAUGAAAGAUCAUUGCAUAUUUAUUGAAUUGUUUAUAUCUACUGUCAAGUUGUUUUGACAUGGAAGAUUUUCAAGUAACAUUGGCAGAGAGGUACAGUAUGUUAUCCCUAUGGUGAAAAUAAAUUAAUUUGUUGUAUAUAGUUCCUCAAUCUCUGAAGUAAAGGUAUGAGUAAUAUAGGGUAUGAAUGGUUUAAUCAAGGCUUUAUUUUGGAAGUAAGAAAAAUGGCAGUGAUGAUUAAAUUGCUGCAGUCCAUAAUUUGGGCUUGUUAUUUGUACAUUAAAGAUUUUUUCCAAGUAAGUUACACUCUGUUAACUUCCUGCUAGCCAUCAGCAUGAGCCCUACUGCCUAAACACUAUUUCAUUUAUUUAUGUUUGGAAACCCCGUAAACAUUUUUGUUUGCAAUCUUGUUUCUUUUGUUAUAAGUCAAGUUUGAAUGUUACAAUACUUUUAUUGAAACUUUUGUUAAGUUUUUUCUUGUAAAUUUUCUUUACUUGUGAGUAUCAUCUUGUCCUUUAAUCCUGUACCCUAAAAUAAGAAAUACAUUUUUGACAGAGGCUUAAUGUUUUAACAAAAGAGUGUGGACAUUUUUAUUUUAAAAUUUAGGCAAAAGUCACUAUCAAAUGGUUGCUUAUUUGUCUCACACAGCCAUAUAGUUUUUCCUGGAGGGUUUUGUUUUGUUGUUGUUGAAAAGACUUUGCUUACAGCUAGAUGAAACUUUCUAUAGAAAAAAAAAAUUGUUGAAAGGUCCAGUUCUCAGUACCAUGUGAGUUAAUGAUACUACAACUAAGUUCUUUUUAAAAAGUGAUUAAUGUAUUUUAUAAAUUACCUUUUCACAUAUGCAAAAUCUGUUUCUACUACAAUGUUAUUUUUACUAAUGCCUUAUUGUUGCACUCUUUUUGAAAUAUCCUGCAGUGAAUAUAUGAAUCAAUUUGGGCUUAAAACUGAAAGCCAGUUGGCUGAAAGGUUUGAAAUACGUACCCCAGUAAAACCAUUCAAUCAAUAAUUGGUAAAUAAUAUUUUAAAAUUGUUUUUAAUCUGUAUAGAUGACAUUUUGUAGCUUUGUACAUGUUGUUAAUUAAGGGCAUAUAAUUUUACACUCAAAGUAUAAUUGCUGAACUCAGGGGUGGGUAGACUUCAAAAAUAUGUCUGCUAUAGAAAUAACUUGAAAAAAAAAAUUAAAACCGUGGCCAGCCACCAAAUUGUGGACACUGUUUAUAUACUGCUAGUUAACAAUUACCACUUUUAAAAAAUUAUAACCGUUUUUGUUCUAUCUUGACUAGAUAAAUUCUCACAAUGAUCUCUGUCAGUUUUAUUAGUUGGCCUGUUUAACCAAGACAGAAAGUCUUUGAAUUACUCAUAGUUUUAAACUGCUUUUAAUAUGAAAAUUGCAGCUGUAAAUUAUGUAUUUUCAUAUUUUGCGUAACUGCUCUACACUACUGUUUGACUUGAUCUUCUUCUGGGGGUUAGGGAGAAAUCUGUCUCCAUAUUGCUGGUUCUCUUACCAAAAUGCUUUUAUAAAGAAAUGACCGGUGACAUUUAUUCACCAAAGGAAUUAAUAUACUGAGUCAAAGAUUAACAAUGCUAUACUAUAGAGUAAUAGGUCAUAUAUAGCCUCAAUUGAGUUUUUUAUGACAAUAUUUUAACAUACCUCUCUCUCUACAUAUAAAUACCAUAAAGUAAACUAAAAUGACACAGAGGAAAGUAGAGGAAAAUGAAAUAAUUUCGGUACAUCUUAUGGUUUAAAGAGUAGAAAAUAAGAUGAAAUAUCCUAAAAUAUAGGAGCACAGACAUUUAAAAUUCAUAAUCAGGCUAACAACACUCUCUUGAAUUUAGGAAUCAUUGAAAACUCCUUGCACUUAGAUUUAAUUUAUAUGUUAGUUACAUUAUUAAAAGUCAUAAGGCAUUUAUCUGAGUCAUUGCUCUACAGAGAGCAAUUAAUGGCUUGUAAUAAUAAAAAGAAUAUUUCUCUGUAAUGCAUUGUUGAAAGACAACCAGAAUAUCAAGAAAAUGUAUAUAGGAAUAUGCUACUUGCCUCCUCCCUGCAUUUCCUCGUGGGGCACUAUUUGCGACAUAGGCCUACAGAAUUAGACUUUCAUACUUAGAAGAUAAGGUACACUCUUCUUCUUUUAUUUAUUUAUUUAUUUAUUUUUAGGCCAUUCUUCUGGUUUGCCAAAUUCUAUUAAGACAGUGAUACAUUUGCUUCCUUAUUUAUGCAUGCUUAGAUCAUGAACAUGAUGCCCUUCUUUUUUUUUUUUUUCUUUGGUCAAGUAGGGAUUAAUGCCAUAGGUUUAGAGAGAAGGAUUGUUUUCAGUUUUUAAGAGAAUUUUUUAAAAAUACAUUUUAUGGUUCUCUUAAGGAAUUAAUAUUCACUUCUGAAGGACUUACUUGUAAUAUAUAAUUUAUCAUUUUAGCCAGCAGGGAAAUAAAUCAUUUUUAAUCCCCAGAAGAAAGUGCUGGAAAUAGCUUCUAUAUAGUCAGCAGUUCACCUGGAGAAAGAUCUUAAUUCCUUGUUGUUUUGACUAGGAAUAUCAAUAUUUGGUAUAAAAUAACUAGAAUAGUUUAUUACCUUUUCCCUCAUGAAAUUUUAAAUAUAUGCAAAUAUAUAUAUCAUUAGAUUCCUGUGGUGGAUAAUAAUUUCUUCAGAUUCUAAAACAGGUGUCUAGUGACUGCUUAAUUGUUUCCAAGUUGCAUCAAAGAUGAAUUGGUAAAUAAUGGAAAUGAGUAGUGAUAUGAAAAUGGUUAUGUAACUACAUAUUACUUGUUUCUGGUAAUCAAGUCUUAUUUUUUAAAAGCCUAUUGUUUUUCAGAAUUGAGAUAUUUAAAACUUGUUAUAACUUCUUCCUAAAAAUAGAAGAGAAGAGGAGGUACUGUGUGUUACAAAAAUUUUUUUAAAUAAAGAAUUCAGUGUCACUAGUUCUAAGCCUUUAUGGUUACUGCUGCUUAUAUUUCUUGAUCUCACUUUCAUUAAUUUUUUUGUACAUAUCUUAGCUGAAUGCUUAAAAUUUACAAUUAUUUGUAAUUGUGUAUGUAAAUUGCUUUUCAAAAAGAACUGAAGCUUAACCAUAUUCUUCUUUUCUGAGGAUUCAUUAUCAGAAUCAGCUACUAUACUGUUCUGUGUUAUAGUAAUGCCGUUACUGCCUGUGCAUGAUUGAGGUCUGUGAAGAAGGUGUCUUUUAAUCUGCACCAACUGGCCCCAAUCCUCUUUGUAGUCCUUUUUAAAUUGUUUUAAAUCUGUCCUUUAUUUUUCUUCCUAUUUUUCUGCCUCUUCCCACUGAUGUCCAAUGUGUCAGUCUUCCGCAGUUUCCUUUUCUCACUUCUAAUUUAUUCUCUCUUUUUUUUUUCUGAGGUUAGGGAUUCUACAGAAGGACGAUUAUUAAAAUUAUGCCAUGAAUUUUUGAAAAAUUUAAAAUGCUCUCCUACAAAUAAAAUACAUGGAGUUUCUGAUACUAAUUUCAGUUUGUCAGUAGAUGGCUAAAUUUGUUGAAUAAUUGACUACUUGGUAAAUGAGCUGUUAGCUGUAAUUAGUUCUUUAGUACUAAUAUUAAGGAAAUUUUGUUAUUUUCGGAUGAGGACUCUCCCAAAGCCAAAUUAUUGUCCAAGCAAAUUAUUUAUUUUUUCCAUUUAAAUUUCUAAGUCAUUUUGAGAUGUGGAAUGAUUAUUUUUAUUAUUUAUUUAUUUAUUUAUUUUUGAGACGGAGUCUUGCUCUGUCACCCGGGCUUUAGUGCAGUGCACGAUCUUGGCUCAUUUCAAUCUCCACCUCCUGGGUCUAAGCGAUUCUCCUGCCUCAGCCUCUUGAGUAGCUGGGAUUACAGGCAUGUGCUGCCACACCUGACUAAUUUUUAGUAGAGACAAGGUUUCACCGUGUUGGCCAGGCUGGUGUUGAACUCCUGACUUCAAGUGAUCUGCCCACCUCAGCCUCCCAAAGUGCUGCGAUUACAGGCAUGACCCACCACACCCAGCCUGGAAUCAUUUUUUAAAAAUAAUUUGUGGGAGACUUGCUUUCUCAACAUAAAUUGUGUGUGGGUUGUUUUUUGUUUUUUGAGACGGUCUUCCUCUGUUGCCCAGGCUGGAGUGUGCAGUGGAACAGUCAUUGCAGCCUUGACCACCUUGGCUCAAGCAAUCCUCCUGCCUCCCGGGUAGCUGAGUCUACAGGUGUGUGCCACCAUGCCUGGAUGGAUAGAAUUUUUUUUUUUUUUUUUUUUUUUUUUUUUUUUUUUAAAGACACGAGGUCUCACCAUGUUGCCCAGGCUGAUCUUGAAUUCCUGGGCUCAAGCAUUCCUCCUGCCUCAGCCUCCCAAAAUGCUGGGAUUACAGGUGCAAGCCACCAUGCCUCGUCUGUUUGCCGAUUUAAGACAGGUUUAUGUACAUCAUUAUCAUUAGAGGCACAUAGAAUCUAGACAUGUACUUGAAACUUAGCUCUCUAUCCUGAAAGUUGAAGUUAGGGUUCUUUGAUCCUGGUGAGAUGUUAAUUGUAAUUUUAAUUUUCAUAUGUUAAUAUUGUGACUUGUAUUUUGUGAUGAGUCUCUAGAAUGAUUAAAUGACUAUUUUUUUAUGAAAAAUUUUUUGUUAAUAAAAUAUCUGAGGGUAUUUUGAGUAUGUGGAAGGAAUGCCUGAAUAGAAGCUGAUCUAUCUUAACAUACCUCAAGAACUCCAGUUUUAAUAUGGUGAGUGAGGAGUUGACUGGGAAAAGGAGAGAUCCAAUUCUUGUUCUAGUCCUUGGCACAUACACUCUCUGGGUUUUGAGAAAAGGAUGGUCCUACAACGAUUCUAAGUUGUUUUCUCAUUGGUCCUACAACAAUUCUAAGUUGUUUUCUCAAAGGCAAAAGCAUGAUUUCAAAAUGACAUCACUUGUCAGAUUUUCUGGUGUAUGGAAAGAUUUAAUAAUCCUGCCUCUUUUGAAGCCUGAAACUUACAAUUUAAAGCCUGAAAUCUACCAUAAGGAACUUGGUAAAUUGUGUCAGAUACCAUGAAAAUGCAUCUUUUCAUAGUUAACCACAGAUUGUUUAUGUAAAGGCAAAUUGGUGGUCAGGUUCAAGGUAAAAUGGAUUAUUGGGUUGAUUAGUAGCCAAAAACUAAAUGCAUGUUCAGGUCAAAAUGAAUUUGUUUGUUUUAGUUGGUGCCAUUUUCCUUUUAUUAUUCAGAACUACAGAGUGUGCAUUUUAUUAAUAGGAAUGAAAGCUCAUGCUUGAGGAUUUGAAUAGGGUGGAUGUAUAUAUUUUAUAAACUCAAGUUGCAAAAUAUGUAAAGUCACUACUUUUUAAAUAGAAUAUAAAUGUUAAAACAGACAAAUCUAUGUUAUAUAUUUUUUAAUACAUGUAUCAGACUUGUUAGUUGAAUGCAGAUUACUUUGCUUUAUGGAAUUUCAUAACUUUUAAUAAUAAAGCAGUUGUUAUUGGAUUUUUUCUGUAGACUUGAAUACUAAAUGGGAUAGAUACCAGACCUCUUUUUGGUUUAUGACGUAAAAGUAUUUGUACAGUAGUUUCUCUUCACAAAAGACUGAAUUUUAAAGGAUUAUAGAAACAGGAACAUGUCCAUUUCCAAAAUGAGUGCAACAGAAUGAAGAUAGUCACUUAAACCAUCUAUUUAACACAUCACCUUUAUGUAAUAUGUAGCUAGUUUUAGUGUUUUAAUAAGUCCCAACUAAAGACUGAGUGUUUUCAGUGAAGAUGGAAAUGGAGACCCAGGCACUUGCUUAGAGUUAUCGUGAGUCCGAUGUUCCUGAACUUCAAGUUGUACAAUUAAGGGCAUACUCUAAGAACUUCUGGAUGCUUUCUGGAGUAUACAAACAGAUCAACUAAUGACUUAAAUGAGUGACUCUUGAAGCUGCAAGAAGAGGAAAGAAAUAACCACAAGAAGGGGCUAUCUCAGCAUCUGUUAUUCCUGACAGGAGGAAUUAAAUAUGCUCUGCUGGUAAUUCUAAGCUUUUCUGCAGGGGAUCUGCUUGCCCCAGGAGCACCUUAGUCCUCAUUGAGGCAGCCAUUCUGCCAUAAAAACGAUCAUGUCUCAAGCUGUUCCUGCCGUCCUACACAACUAUGUUAGUAGAUGGUUAGAUAAAUAUAUGAACCAUCUUUUGUACUUUGAUGAUGCCCUUUUCCUUUAUUAUAAUCCUUAAUUUCUACUUUCCAUAGUAGGAUUUGACUUUUCUCCAUUAGUUUAAGCUACCCUGGAUAAGUGACUCUGUUUAUGUCCUCCCUAUAUUUCUUACUCAUUUUCACACUAACAUAACACGUAACAAAAUUAAACAUAAGCUAAAUUGAAGAAGCAAGUGAGACAGCUAAGAGUUUUGUGUACUUGGACAACAAAGCUCAAAGCCACUGUGGUUAUCUGUCCUGUUGGGAGCCCCUUUCAACCAUUUUUUUAGUUGCCUGUAAGAUUUAUUUUUAAUGUUUGCCUGCAUAAUGCAAAAUACAUAAGUGGGAAUCCCUACGCCCUUUACAGUUAAGUGGAUUAUGGAAAUAAUAAGGAAAGUUUAUCAACUAAGGUAGGAAAUAUCUUCUCAUGUCUGUAUCUGGCCUUCAGGGACUUAAUGUGGGUGAAUAUAUGUCAUUAGACAAGAUCCUAAUAUAGAUGGCUGUAUCCUGCAGAUAGCCAAUUCAACAUUAAAAUUUUAUGUUUCCAUACCUCAAUGAAAACAUAUUUCUUUUAUCCUGUUAUAAUUUAAUGACAUUCCCAUCCAACUUAAUCAAGCAAUGAUACUCAGUAGUCCUCUCCUUGCAUUUUUCAAGUCCUGUUGAGUGUAACUUUAAAAUGUCUCUGAGAUUUCUACCUUCUCUCCAGUCUCCUUACCAUUAGGGCCUUUCACUACCUGGCCUUGGUGUCCCUAGGCUGCUCUUCAGCUGUCCACAAACCUUGUUUCAUAAGCAGUAGCAAUGCAAGCUUCCACUGCCGUCUGCUAAUGUUCUUCCCUCCUAGAAUGUUCAUGAUCUGCGUUUCUACCUGAAAGGUCUAGUUCAAAGGUAGCUGAAAGGUUAUCAUCCUUGUCCUUUCUUCUCUCCCUACCAGUCAUCUAUCCUGAACUUUUUAACAGUAGGGACAGUGUUGCAAUUGUGUUUGUGUCCCCAGCACGUAGCACACAGUACCUAGUAUACAGUACCUGUAGCACAUAGGCAUUUAAUAAGUGUGUAUUGAAUUAACUUGGUUAUGCUUGUAUUUUUAUCCUAGCUUUCUCAAAGAAACUUAGGUGCUAGCUAUUUUGAAACAUAUAUCCAGAACCACCACCUGAGUAAAAUGUAUAACAGGACCCUGCUCUUUCUAUCCCAGAGAGUUUGAGAAAACUACUUUUAAAUAAAUCAUUAAUCAUUCUUCA